GGAAACCGCCCCGGCGGCUGAGAGGCUGCGGCCACUGCCUGGCACCCCGACGGGAGGGGCUCCGGAUCGUUCGGAGCCGGCUGAACCCCUUCGGCCGCGAGCGACCGCAUGAGUCGGGGGACUAUGCCCCAGCCCGAAGCGUGGCCAGGCGCGAGCUGCGCCGAGACGCCGGCGCGGGAGGCGGCGGCCACGGCGCGGGACGGCGGGAAGGCGGCGGCCAGCGGGCAGCCGCGGCCCGAGAUGCAGUGCCCGGCCGAGCAUGAGGAGGACAUGUACCGUGCUGCAGAUGAAAUAGAAAAGGAGAAAGAAUUGCUUAUACAUGAAAGAGGGGCAUCAGAACCGAGAUUAAGCGUAGCUCCUGAAAUGGAUAUCAUGGACUACUGCAAAAAAGAAUGGAGAGGAAAUACACAGAAAGCAACGUGUAUGAAAAUGGGCUAUGAAGAGGUUUCUCAGAAGUUCACCUCCAUACGGCGAGUCCGUGGUGAUAAUUACUGUGCACUGAGGGCCACGCUGUUCCAGGCCAUGAGCCAGGCUGUGGGGCUGCCGCCCUGGCUGCAGGACCCGGAGCUCAUGCUGUUACCAGAAAAACUCAUAAGCAAAUACAACUGGAUCAAGCAAUGGAAACUUGGACUGAAAUUUGAUGGGAAGAAUGAGGACCUGGUUGAUAAAAUUAAAGAGUCCCUUACUCUGCUGAGGAAGAAGUGGGCAGGCUUGGCUGAAAUGAGAACUGCUGAAGCAAGACAGAUAGCUUGUGAUGAACUAUUCACAAAUGAGGCGGAGGAAUAUAGCCUCUAUGAAGCUGUAAAAUUUCUAAUGCUAAACAGAGCCAUUGAACUAUAUAAUGAUAAAGAGAAAGGAAAGGAAGUACCAUUUUUCUCUGUGCUUCUGUUUGCUCGGGACACAUCAAAUGACCCAGGACAGCUUCUGAGGAACCACCUCAACCAGGUGGGACACACUGGUGGUCUUGAACAGGUUGAAAUGUUCCUUCUUGCCUAUGCUGUGCGCCACACCAUCCAGGUGUACCGGCUCUCCAAGUACAACACGGAAGAAUUCAUCACAGUCUACCCCACCGACCCACCCAAGGACUGGCCAGUGGUAACGCUCAUUGCUGAGGACGAUCGGCACUAUAACAUCCCCGUCAGAGUGUGUGAGGAGACCAGUCUAUGAGAGACGCAUGCUCCUGACAGCCUGGCGACGUGGCGAAGAUGCACAGGUGGCUCCUGGGCUUGGGCUGCAGGUUUGGGGGUCUCUAAGAACAAUCUCUGAGAAGAACCCUUGGGCCCCUGGGAGCCAAGUUGGACAGGAUGUCCUGAAGACUAGCUUUUGAUAAGAGAAAUUAACCAAGUCUUUCCCCUCAUCUAUGAUGCAAUAUAUUUCAGUGGGGGCCUUCAGAGCACACCUGUUGGACGGUGCAAACCAUAUCUUCUCCAGAAGGCAAAUACUUUUGUAUCAGAGGAAACUCAGUUUUGGAGAGGAAUAUGUUCUUUAUGUCUCAAAUCAAAACUCUCUCUAAUGGUAAACUGGCUUCUAAUUUUUUUAAGUACAGUAUUUUUUUUUCCCCUUUAGUAGUAACGGGUUUCUAUAGAUCUUCCUAUACAGUCUGCUUUAACUCAGGACCUUGAGAUUAUGAGACUGACGUGCUGCCCACUGCACUGAGGGGGCUUCUAACAGUCUGCUUUAAGUGGUAUAAUUCUGGGAUAGAUCUGUUACUGGCAUAGUCAUGACAACCUCUGGUAAUCUUACCUUCUCCUUUUUAUGAAGGGAAGAGCAAUGGUUUGGACUUACAUCUUAAUUAAGGCUAUUUUAAGCAGAUUGUUUUGCAACAGAUUAAGAAUUGGGUCCCAAAGUGGGUUAUUUCAAGGCAUUUUUGAAGACUGGAGGAGCGUAGGAGGGAGUGGUGAGGGAACCUAGAACUUCUUGCUCCUUGUGACUAUGACAGAUGUCUGAUGCCCCCAGCGCACUGGAGUCUGGGGCUUGGUGCAGGUGGUGCCCCAUCAGUGUGGACAGACACUACUUGCCUUUGUGGUUUAGUGUUGGAAGCUUUAAUUAUUCUACAGUUCCAUAGAUUCACAAUUUUAUAGCCAAACAGUUUGUAUCCACCUGCUUUCAGAGGAGGAACCAAAGGCCAAAUUACUUUGAGGUAGGGCUUAGCUGGACCUGGGUUUUCCUAUGCUCUUUUCAUGCUGUGUUGGAGGGUGUGUCCACUGCCAGAUCUGUGUAACCCGUCUGGGUCAGGGGAUGAGUGACAGCAAACCAUCUUAAAAUUUUUCAUGAGUACAUUUAAGCGGAAGCAUACGGGAAUAUGAGUGCAAAAGUGUGGCUGAGCCGCGUAUGCCCUUGAUUGGUUUUGGGAAGCCUGAGGGAGGCAGCCUUCCUGGCUAUGAGCCAUCGCCUGCCCAAUCAGGCUAAGGGUGGUGACUGGGGUGGUGAAGGGGCAGCUCUGCUGAGCAUGGUCUGCCUUAUGGCCUGAAUUGUCCUCAAGGGGUGUGGACUGCAGAUGGUGUUCACAUGAACCGGAGACAUCACUCUUUAGGAUUCUACUGGCAGCCCCUGAAUUGGCUCAACGUUUGUGGAGGUGGUAUUUCCCUGAAGUACUGAGCUUUGUUUUAUAAUAAUUAAAAUCCUUAUUUGGUCCAAUUUAAUAUAGUUUAGAAGCUAUUUUUUUUGAGGCAAACCGUUUUUGAAAAUGUAAAUUUUGUUUUUAAUUAAAAAUAAAGUCUUAGUUAAGAAAACUCAGGAUGCACAAAACUAUUCAGACUGUUACUUUAGCUUUCUCCCAUUACCUCAUCAGUAAUAUUCACCACAUUUUGCUAAAUAUUUAUUGAUUAGAGUGUUGAAAUCAAAUUCUGCUCUAAAUGUGUGUGAAUAUGUUGGAGAGGCUUUGUGUUCUUCACUGUGAAAUGCAAUUGUGCCUUGAAUAAGAAGGUACCUAGAAGCCAAAUUAAAGUAAUAAUGACUUCUUAUUGGCUUUGAUUUUUCAUUGCAGUAUAUGGGAUUGUACAGCAGGAAAUGCUUAUCAUUAAUUUCUGAUGUUUUUUAAAGCACAACUCGAAACAUUUCGAUCAUACAUACAUAGCAGUAGAGAUCUGUGCCCUUCAGGUACAUUGAAUCUGACCAUCAGUUUAUAUAUGUCAUUGAAUUUUAAGAAUACUCAUGUUAAUAAUAGUCAUCUAUCCUUGCAUUUUGAAACUGUUCUAAUCUUAGUGAACUUGAAUUGGAUUUCUGGGUAAAAGAAUGUGUUUCUUUUAUGUUGCUUAUGUCCGAAGGCCUUGUCAGAAUCUGUCAGACUCUUGUUUAGGUUUAGUGUGAUCAUGGCGUCAGAGAAGCAAAGCUUUCAAAUAAAUAGUACUUCAGGAAAUAGAAAUGAUUGACCAACUUUAAAAAUAAUUUUUUUUUAAUUGCAAUAUGCAGCUUCAGUUGCCCAGAAUCUUAGUUCCGUUUCUCAUUCUUGGUCUUGAGCUGGUCAGGUGACAUCAGCAGAUUAGAAGUUGAAUGGAGAUUAAGUGGAUUCAGGAGGAUGUUCCACUUAGAGCAGUCUUCAAAAUGAUAAGGUGUUCUAGAAGAAAGGAAUGUAGUAGGAACUAUACUAUGCCUAACUUUCUAUCCCAGAGUGUCUUGCAAGAGUUUAGGAGUUUUGGACCCUGUGUAUUGGCAGAAAAGUUAUCUCCAUCUUAAGCAGGCAUGACUUUUAUACCUGUGAGCUCAUUUAAGGUGCAUUUAAACCUAAAAUAAUUUCCCUGUAUUAUGCUUCAUGGGAUUAACACUGCUUUUCCAGAACAUUUUCAGAUUCCCCUCCUUACAUCCUGAGCUCCUUCUGUAUAUACAUCUGUUGAUUUUAUCCAUCCACAAGGAACAAUGAUAGUCACAUUAGAGAACAAGAAACCAGUAAUACAUGGUCUCUAACUGAUGAUUCGGGCCUGGAUUUGAUUGAAAGUGUUUGCAGUUCCUCUUCCGUAGAAUACAGAGUGGAUGAAAAUGUUUUCAAUGCACAGAACAGGAUGAAUCCUUUUUUCUUUAUUUAGCGAUUUACACUUUUGUUACUCUAUUAUAUAUUCAGUUAGUGUCUGAUAAGAUUUUCUUUGCUUAAGGAGAACGGACAUUGCCUUGGUAUGUUUUUUUUUUUUUUUCCCUCCACUUUUGGAGCUUAUCAGGUAAAAAUCUCAAGCCACAUGAAUUGUUAACACCUCUGUUGGGAAAAGCCUUUGUGAGUUUUUAUGUACUUGGUCUUUGUUUUUGUUAUUCAUCCUGUGUCCUCCCUCUUCCCGAUGUGCUGUUUUACCUAGGAGUUAGUCUGCUUUCUGAGGAUCUUUUAGAGAGAGGCUGUGAAGUGCUGAAUCACCUUUAAUGAUACAGCACUUCUGCCAUCUCAGCAUCUACAUAGGACUUACAUAGACUUCCUGAAUGUGUCUUCUUCAGAUACUAAAGUACAGUUGGAUCAUUUUCUUAUCUCCUUUUCUUAAGCAGUACUUUGCAGGUACUCCCCUUUGAAAGCCAGAAGCAUAAACCAUUGGGGAAUCUUAACUUGUAGACAUGCAGUAAAAGAAAUGCAUUUAUGUAAGAUCUGUGAGUACUUAAAAAGAAAGCCCUCAGUGUGUGUGAAGUGAAUGUGAAAUGUGUGUGAAAUACAUAGAAUUCCCAAAUAGUUUAGCAAAGGCAGGGCGCAAUAUCAAGUAAUUUAAAAAUGGUCCAAGGAACUGUAAGAAGGAGGAACUAAUUCUAGAAUAAAUGUUAAAAUGCCAUUCAAGAACAAAACCACAGAUGCCAUACAGACCUCCUGUGCUUAAGUUAUAGAAGAAUAAAAAUCUGAAUGAAUGGAAGGCCUUACGUGUAUACAGUUUACAAAUUCCUAUUUCUAAAAUUUAAGUCCCUUAUUUAACAGAAGUAUGUAUUUUAAUGCUUAACUGUCUCGGGAAACCUCAUUUGUGACAUCAUCUAAGGGGAUGGGAAGACUAGGGAGCCAGUGCCACGUUGAACAGAACAGUGGUUUAGUGAAUGUGUGAGGAAAGACAUGGGCAACUGAUUAUUAAUGUUUUUGUAAUUCAGUUUAUAACUUGGAACCAAUGAAAAGCAACAAAACUAAACUGGUUUGACAGCCUGCCACUUCUGGCAUUUCCUGUAAGUCACUAGCAGUAGGUGUGAGGUGGGCUUGCCCAUGACCAGGAGGGGUGUGUGUGUGUGUGUGCAUGUGUGUAUAUGCGUGUUGGUCUGCAGUCACAGCAUACCUUUAUGUGCAUGUGUCCUCGCAGCUUGGGACUCAGCAGUAUUCUGGGAGGGUGGAGGUGAACUGUCCCAUGUAUUGUAUUAUAUAUUUUUUGAGAUGGGGUCUUGCUCUGUUGCCCAGGCUGGAGUGCAGUGGUGCGAUCUCAGCUCACUGCAACUUUUGCCUCCUGGUUCAAGCAGUUCUCCUGCCUCAGCCUGCCAAAUAGCUGGGAUUACAGGUGUGUACCACCACUCCCAGCUAAUUUUUGUAUUUUUAGUAGAGAUGGGGUUUUACCAUGUUGGCCAGGCUGGUCUCGAGCUCCUGGCCUCAGGUGAUCCACCUGCUUUGGCCUCCCAAAGUGCUGAGAUUACAGGCGUGAACUACCGCGCCUGGCCCCAUGUAUUGUAUUUUUUUCAGGUUAUAUUGAAAUCUACUACCAGGAAUGUCGGAAUGGGUUUUGGUAUGUAUAAUGGAAAUAGAUAGAGUGGUUAAGUCUAGAAACACAUACAUUAAUUGUAUUGAAAUGUUAUAUCAAUACAUCAUUUAUGAUGUGUGUGUGGUCCCAGACCUCAUGGCCACCAGUUUGUUUAAGCAUUGUGAAUGCUUUUUAAUAGCAUUCAUUAGCAUUAAUGGAGGAGGACACUGUGUUUUCUCAAUUAAUCUCAUUGAUUUGUUUGGUAUAAGUUUGGGUCAGAAAUGAAACUGCCAAAACAUCGAUCAGUACAAGGAAGGGACACAGGGCUUAAAAUGUCCACAGUCUUGGCAGUGGACUUGGCAGUUCUCCCAGUAAGCAGAAGUACUUGAGCUUAAUUCUGAACUUCAAAGUAAUAUUUUAUACUUAAUUUUAGGAGUUUUCAUUUACAUAUUGAAAAAUGCCUUGACUGUAUUCACAUAAAUGGUGCUAAAACAUUGUACCCCUUAUAAGAACUGCAGCAAUCCACAGUAAUGUUGGUUACUUCUGAGUAUUUGAUAAAGGAACAAAGUCAAAAUGAAUGUAUUUAAUAAGCUUCUUUCUCAUUUCCAUUGUUUUUAUAAAAAUAUUUUGGUAUUGUUGCCUGCAUUUUAGCCACUUCUAACUUUUUGUAUUAUGAAUUUGGAGAGGAUAACAAGCCAACUUUAGACCCUCUGCCAGUGGCGAUGGUGUUUUUCUUCCAUGGGUAAGCCAUUGUGAAUGGAGGCUGGUGGAGCAGCACACUGUGUGAACCUGGCAGCGCUCAUCUUGGCUUGUUUAGCAGUGCCUCUGUUUACACCAUAAGAUGUUCCGCAUGUGUCCAAAAUUUCGCCUGCUCUGAAAAACAUGCCCCCGAGGCUCUGUGCAGUUUGGGGCCUUGGUUCCCACCUGCAGAUGCGGUCAGUUGCCUGGCUCCUGGGGCCAGAGUUUCCUCUGUUACUUGUUGAGUCUCUUGUCUUCACUGUCAGAAGCUGAACUGACUUGGGGGCUUUGCUGUUGAUCCACUUUAGCAAACCCUGCUGCAGAGGACUGUAAAAACAAAUAACUAAAAAUAAACUUAGAAAAUACAACUCAGAAGCCUGGCUCUGUUGCUGUGGUCAAAUGCUUGCCUUUGAGGACUUUGGCAGAUUGUGCUAUUACAUUGGGCUCUAACUUUCUGGCACCCGCAAGGCAGACCUAUGAUGUCCACAUGGCUGACUCUUGACCCCUGGCCAUUGUGAGCAGAGGAAUCAAGGGUUUAGGGAGGCAGUAUUGGGCAGUGUGGAAGAGUUAGAUGAGAUGAAGCAGUUAGCACAGUGCUUAACCCAUACUAAGUGCCCCCAACCCUGCCAGCCAAAUUAGGUGCAUAGUUUUCAGCUUGGGUCUGGAUUCAACAGCAUUCCCGCUGCCCACUAAAAGGGUGGGCUUGGACAGUUCCUGAACCUCCCUAAAUCUGUUUCUUCAUCUUUACCACACACAGUCUGUCUCAGUGGUGGUGUGGAUUAAGUGAGGUGCUAGCACUUAUUAGGGGAAGAUCCUCCAGACCUGCAAAGCAGGGCUGCAGCCCCAAUUCUGACCCAGCCCUGCUGUGUGUUUGCCGCAAAGAGGUUUGGUGUGUGCGAGACAUUUCUUUAUGAACCAUUUACACUGCUGGAAAUGUACCCACUAAUGUGAUGGCAAGAACUUCAACAAAUUGCUUAUGAAUCAGGCUCUCAAUGGAAGAAGUUAAUCCUCUGAAGAGGGGGAAGACUGGACUUUCAGAAGUAUGUUGGGGAUAGAGAAUGAAGUUUGAGUCAGCAGAGCUCUGCCUUCCUGUUUGUCAAAGAACUAGAGUCUGGGAGUCUUGCAAGAUGGAGCUGGGCUUCUGAAGAACCCAGUGGGUAGGUACUGGGCAUCCAUUAGACGGCAGUGCUAAGUCGGUCAUGUGCAGCAGAAAGACCUCCCCACUGUGAACAACAAACCACUUUCCUCCUCCAGUGGCCCAUUCAUUUGGAUUGAUACACUUUUUCAGUGUCAGAAAUGCACUUUCUCCCUCUACUUGUCUGAAUUACGAUGCUCUGCUCAACUCUGUGGACAGUGUUUCUUGAAUUUCCUUUUCCACCGCCUUUUCCCACUCAAGAAAGUGGAGAGAAAAACAGGGAUGCAGGCUGUGGGUCUUGUGGAAGCCCUUUACAACCAUUAAAUAAAGAACACCAGCUGCAUUAUGUGUGUUUAGAACGAGAAGUUGUUUGUACAGUAUUUUUCUAUUGACCGCUUCCGUCUUGCCUGAAACCUGGGCAUUCUUUCUGUAGUUUCUCUGAAUUUUCUGUCUCACCUCCUCACCCCUACCCUUGCCUUUU